ACACCUGUUUCCUAGUGCUGCAGAACCCUCGUCCUGGGAUGAGCCUGCCCGCUAGUCUGCAUCCUAAUCCUGCUGUUGAUUGGAGAUAACUUCAGCGGUCACAGGGCACCUCGUCUCCAUGGCAACCCCUCUAAAUAUUCCUCUAGUGACUUGUGCUCUACAUUCUGGCUGGAUCAGAGCCCUCCUGUGGCAAAAUAUUCUAAAGAUGUUAAAAGAGAGAGAGAGAAAAAAAAAGGCUCAACUAAUAAAUCUAUUCUAAACGACUGAGUCAUUUGUUUUGAUUACCCGGGUGAUUGCCAAAUGUUAAUUUAAAACUGAAAUAGGCCAUGAGCUCACUCCCCUAACAAUGCUGAGUGUUUGAGCUAAUACGGCUUGAUAAUGAGGGAGCCAGAUCCACUGCCAGUGCUCAUGUUAUAUGAUAAACAGACAUUUGGAGAAGUAUGCAGAACAUCUUGGCAGUUUUCCUUUAACUCUAAGGGUUGUAAAUACAAAGUAGAAUGUGUUACCAUGAGCCAUUUCAUAGGAAGUUGACUUUAUUUUUUUAGAAUUCAGAACUUUGCUUCUAAAAAGGUAACUUUGCCUCUUGAUUCUCAUUUUUUUCCCUAACUUAGGCACCUUGGAAGUUGUUUUCAACCAUAUCCAGCCUUUGCCGAAUACAUCCUAUCUGCCACACAUCCAGCGUGAGGUCCCUCCAGCUACAAGGUGGGCACCAUGGCGGAGAAGUUUGACUGCCACUACUGCAGGGAUCCCUUGCAGGGGAAGAAGUAUGUGCAAAAGGAUGGCCACCACUGCUGCCUGAAAUGCUUUGACAAGUUCUGUGCCAACACCUGUGUGGAAUGCCGCAAGCCCAUCGGUGCGGACUCCAAGGAGGUGCACUAUAAGAACCGCUUCUGGCAUGACACCUGCUUCCGCUGUGCCAAGUGCCUUCACCCCUUGGCCAAUGAGACCUUUGUGGCCAAGGACAACAAGAUCCUGUGCAACAAGUGCACCACUCGGGAGGACUCCCCCAAGUGCAAGGGGUGCUUCAAGGCCAUUGUGGCAGGAGAUCAAAACGUGGAGUACAAGGGGACCGUCUGGCACAAAGACUGCUUCACCUGUAGUAACUGCAAGCAAGUCAUCGGGACUGGAAGCUUCUUCCCUAAAGGGGAGGACUUCUACUGCGUGACUUGCCAUGAGACCAAGUUUGCCAAGCAUUGCGUGAAGUGCAACAAGGCCAUCACAUCUGGAGGAAUCACUUACCAGGAUCAGCCCUGGCAUGCCGAUUGCUUUGUGUGUGUUACCUGCUCUAAGAAGCUGGCUGGGCAGCGUUUCACCGCUGUGGAGGACCAGUAUUACUGCGUGGAUUGCUACAAGAACUUUGUGGCCAAGAAGUGUGCUGGAUGCAAGAACCCCAUCACUGGGUUUGGUAAAGGCUCCAGUGUGGUGGCCUAUGAAGGACAAUCCUGGCACGACUACUGCUUCCACUGCAAAAAAUGCUCCGUGAAUCUGGCCAACAAGCGCUUUGUUUUCCACCAGGAGCAAGUGUAUUGUCCCGACUGUGCCAAAAAGCUGUAAACUGACAGGGGCUCCUGUCCUGUAAAAUGGCAUUUGAAUCUCGUUCUUUGUGUCCUUACUUUCUGCCCUAUACCAUCAAUAGGGGAAGAGUGGUCCUUCCCUUCUUUAAAGUUCUCCUUCCGUCUUUUCUCCCAUUUUACAGUAUUACUCAAAUAAGGGCACACAGUGAUCAUAUUAGCAUUUAGCAAAAAGCAACCCUGCAGCAAAGUGAAUUUCUGUCCGGCUGCAAUUUAAAAAUGAAAACUUAGGUAGAUUGACUCUUCUGCAUGUUUCUCAUAGAGCAGAAAAGUGCUAAUCAUUUAGCCACUUAGUGAUGUAAGCAAGAAGCAUAGGAGAUAAAACCCCCACUGAGAUGCCUCUCAUGCCUCAGCUGGGACCCACCGUGUAGACACACGACAUGCAAGAGUUGCAGCGGCUGCUCCAACUCACUGCUCACCCUCUUCUGUGAGCAGGAAAAGAACCCUACUGACAUGCAUGGUUUAACUUCCUCAUCAGAACUCUGCCCUUCCUUCUGUUCUUUUGUGCUUUCAAAUAACUAACACGAACUUCCAGAAAAUUAACAUUUGAACUUAGCUGUAAUUCUAAACUGACCUUUCCCCGUACUAACGUUUGGUUUCCCCGUGUGGCAUGUUUUCUGAGCGUUCCUACUUUAAAGCAUGGAACAUGCAGGUGAUUUGGGAAGUGUAGAAAGACCUGAGAAAACGAGCCUGUUUCAGAGGAACAUCGUCACAACGAAUACUUCUGGAAGCUUAACAAAACUAACCCUGCUGUCCUUUUUAUUGUUUUUAAUUAAUAUUUUUGUUUUAAUUGAUAGCAAAAUAGUUUAUGGGUUUGGAAACUUGCAUGAAAAUAUUUUAGCCCCCUCAGAUGUUCCUGCAGUGCUGAAAUUCAUCCUACGGAAGUAACCGCAAAACUCUAGAGGGGGAGUUGAGCAGGCGCCAGGGCUGUCAUCAACAUGGAUAUGACAUUUCACAACAGUGACUAGUUGAAUCCCUUGUAACGUAGUAGUUGUCUGCUCUUUGUCCAUGUGUUAAUGAGGACUGCAAAGUCCCUUCUGUUGUGAUUCCUAGGACUUUUCCUCAAGAGGAAAUCUGGAUUUCCACCUACCGCUUACCUGAAAUGCAGGAUCACCUACUUACUGUAUUCUACAUUAUUAUAUGACAUAGUAUAAUGAGACAAUAUCAAAAGUAAACAUGUAAUGACAAUACAUACUAACAUUCUUGUAGGAGUGGUUAGAGAAGCUGAUGCCUCAUUUCUACAUUCUGUCAUUAGCUAUUAUCAUCUAACGUUUCAGUGUAUCCUUACAGAAAUAAAGCAGCAUAUGAAUAACCUGC